AGUUCUGCAUUUCUGCAGAGACAGAAAGAAACGCAGCUCUUGACUUCUUUUUUGUAAACAUUACUGUAAGAGUUGUGAUAACUUUUUAUUCUACUAUGUAUAUGUAUGGAAUAGUAUUAAUAAAUGAACUAGGGAAGGAUGUAAUAAAUUAGACAUCUCUUCAUUUUAGAGAGAAGAUGGAAACAACAUUGCUUUUCUUUUCUCAAAUAAAUAUGUGUGAAUCAAAAGAAAAAACUUUUUUCAAGUUAAUACAUGGUUCAGGAAAAGAAGAAACAAGCAAAGAAGCCAAAAUCAGAGCUAAGGAAAAAAGAAAUAGACUAAGUCUUCUUGUGCAGAAACCUGAGUUUCAUGAAGACACCCGCUCCAGUAGAUCUGGGCACUUGGCCAAAGAAACAAGAGUCUCCCCUGAAGAGGCAGUGAAAUGGGGUGAAUCAUUUGACAAACUGCUUUCCCAUAGAGAUGGACUAGAGGCUUUUACCAGAUUUCUUAAAACUGAAUUCAGUGAAGAAAAUAUUGAAUUUUGGAUAGCCUGUGAAGAUUUCAAGAAAAGCAAGGGACCUCAACAAAUUCACCUUAAAGCAAAAGCAAUAUAUGAGAAAUUUAUACAGACUGAUGCCCCAAAAGAGGUUAACCUUGAUUUUCACACAAAAGAAGUCAUUACAAACAGCAUCACUCAACCUACCCUCCACAGUUUUGAUGCUGCACAAAGCAGAGUGUAUCAGCUCAUGGAACAAGACAGUUAUACACGUUUUCUGAAAUCUGACAUCUAUUUAGACUUGAUGGAAGGAAGACCUCAGAGACCAACAAAUCUUAGGAGACGAUCACGCUCAUUUACCUGCAAUGAAUUCCAAGAUGUACAAUCAGAUGUUGCCAUUUGGUUAUAAAGAAAAUUGAUUUUGCUCAUUUUUAUGACAAACUUAUACAUCUGCUUCUAACAUAUCGCAUGUUUAUGUUAAGAUUUGGUCCCAUCCUUUAAACUGAAAUAUGUCAUGUGAAAUUAUUUUAAAAAUGUAAAAACAAAACUUUCUGCUAACAAAAUACAUACAGUAUCUGCCAGUAUAUUCUGUAAAACCUUCUAUUUGAUGUCAUUCCAUUUAUAAUCAGAAAAAAAACUUAUUUCUUAAUCAAAAGGCAGUACAAAAAAAGUAAUAAUGUUUUAUAAGAUUGUAGAGUUAAGUAAAAGUUAAGCUUUUGCAAAGUUGUCAAAAGUUCAAACAAAAGUCUAGUUGGGAUUUUUUACCAAAGCAGCAUAAUAUGUGUUAUAUAAACAUAAUAAUACUCAGAUAUCCAAAUGUUCAGAUAGCAUUUUUCAUAAUGAAUGUUCUCUUUUUUUUGGUAAUAGUGUAGAAGUGAUCUGGUUCUUACAAUGGGAGAUGAAGAACAUUUAUUAUUGGGUUACUACUAACCCUGUCCCAAGAAUAGUAAUAUCACCUCUAGUUAUAAGCCAGCAACAGGAACUUUUGUGAAGACACAUUCAUCUCUACAGAACUUCAGAUUAAAUAUAAUCUAGAUUAAUGACUGAGAAUAAGAUCCACAUUUGAACUCAUUCCUAAGUGAACAUGGACGUACCCAGUUAUACAAAGUACUUCUGUUGGUCACAGAAACAUGACCAGAUUUUGCAUAUCUCCAGGUAGGGAACUAAGUAGACUACCUUAUCACCGGCUAAGAAAACUUGCUACUAAACUAUUAGGCCAUCAAUGGCUUGAAUAAAAACCAGAGAAGGUUUUUCCCAGGACGUCUCAUGUUUGGCCCUUUAGAAUUGGGGUAGAAAUCAGAAAUGAGAUGAGGGGAAGAAGCAAGGAGUCUAAGGCCCUAGCGAUUUGGGCAUCUGCCACAUUGGUUCAUAUUCAGAAAGUGUUAUCUCAUUGAUUAUAUUCUUGUUAAGCAAAUCUCCUUAAGUAAUUAUUAUUCAAAUAAGAUUAUACUCAUACAUCUAUAUGUCACUGUUUUAAAGAGAUAUUUAAUUUUUAAUGUGUGUUACAUGGUCUGUAAAUAUUUGUAUUUAAAAAUGCCAUGCAUUAGGCUUUGGAAAUUUAAUGUUAGUUGAAAUGUAAAAUGUGAAAACUUUAGAUCAUUUGUAGUAAUAAAUAUUUUUAACUUCAUUCAUACAGUUAAGUUUAUCUGACAAUAAAAGCUCUGACUGAA